GAAGAUAUGUAGGGCAUGGGCCUUUCACAAAGCAACAGCUCUACCCUUACCUGCCGCCCACUUUCCAUUUUCCCUGCAUCACUCACCUGCUCUGUGCUUGCUAGACCAAACAGCCAAACAGCUGACAUUCGCUGUCACUCCUGCUACAAGGUCCCUGUGCUGGGCUGUGUGGACCGGCAGUCCUGCCGCCUGGAGCCAGGACAGCAAUGCCUGACAACACAUGCAUACCUUGGUAAGAUGUGGGUUUUCUCCAAUCUGCGCUGUGGCACACCAGAAGAGCCCUGUCAGGAGGCCUUCAACCAAACCAACCGUAAGCUGGGUCUGACAUAUAACACCACCUGCUGCAACAAGGACAACUGCAACAGCGCAGGACCCCGGCCCACUCCAGCCCUGGGCCUUGUCUUCCUUACCUCCUUGGCUGGCCUUGGCCUCUGGCUGCUGCACUGAGACUCAUUCCAUUGGCUGCCCCUCCUCCCACCUGCCUUGGCCUGAGCCUCUCUCCCUGUGUCUCUGUAUCCCCUGGCUUUACAGAAUCGUCUCUCCCUAGCUCCCAUUUCUUUAAUUAAACACUGUUCCGAGUGGUCUCCUCAUCCAUCCUUCCCACCUCACACCCUUCACUCUCCUUUUUCUGGGUCCCUUCCCACUUCCUUCCAGGACCUCCAUUGGCUCCUAGAAGGGCUCCCCACUUUGCUUCCUAUACUCUGCUGUCCCCUACUUGAGGAGGGAUUGGGAUCUGGGCCUGAAAUGGGGCUUCUGUGUUGUCCCCAGUGAAGGCUCCCACAAGGACCUGAUGACCUCACUGUACAGAGCUGACUCCCCAAAUCCAGGCUCCCAUAUGUACCCCAUCCCCCAUACUCACCUCUUUCCAUUUUGAGUAAUAAAUGUCUGAGUCUGA